ACCGGUGAGUCGCCGGCGCUGCAGAGGGAGGCGGCACUGGUCUCGACGUGGGGCGGCCAGCGAUGAAGCCGCCCAGUUCAAUACAAACAAGUGAGUUUGACUCAUCAGAUGAAGAGCCUAUUGAAGAUGAACAGACUCCAAUUCAUAUAUCAUGGCUAUCUUUGUCACGAGUGAAUUGUUCUCAGUUUCUCGGUUUAUGUGCUCUUCCAGGUUGUAAAUUUAAAGAUGUUAGAAGAAAUGUCCAAAAAGAUACAGAAGAACUAAAGAGCUGUGGUAUACAAGACAUAUUUGUUUUCUGCACCAGAGGGGAACUGUCAAAAUAUAGAGUCCCAAACCUUCUGGAUCUCUACCAGCAAUGUGGAAUUAUCACCCAUCAUCAUCCAAUCGCAGAUGGAGGGACUCCUGACAUAGCCAGCUGCUGUGAAAUAAUGGAAGAGCUUACAACCUGCCUUAAAAAUUACCGAAAAACCUUAAUACACUGCUAUGGAGGACUUGGGAGAUCUUGUCUUGUAGCUGCUUGUCUCCUACUAUACCUGUCUGACACAAUAUCACCAGAGCAAGCCAUAGACAGCCUGCGAGACCUAAGAGGAUCCGGGGCAAUACAGACCAUCAAGGAUCUACCUACUUCUCAGUUUUUGCCCCAGUCCGUUUUGGGAAUGGAUCCUCUCACCUAGGACAAUGAGAUGGUUAUUGUUAAUACAAACUUGCAAUACAAUUAUCUUCAUGAGUUUCGGGACAAAUUAGCUGCACAUCUAUCAUCAAGAGAUUCACAAUCAAGAUCUGUAUCAAGAUAAAGGAAUUCAAAUAGCAUAUAUAUGACCAUGUCUGAAAUGUCAGUUCUCUAGCAUAAUUUGUAUUGAAAUGAAACCACCAGUGUUAUCAACUUGAAUGUAAAUGUACAUGUGCAGAUAUUCCUAAAGUUUUAUUGACAAAA